CCACAAAUGUGGGAGGGCGAUAACCACUCGUAGAAAGCGUGAGAAGUUACUACAAGCGGUCCUCCCGGCCACCGUACUGUUCCGCUCCCAGAAGCCCCGGGCGGCGGAAGUCGUCACUCUUAAGAAGGGACGGGGCCCCACGCUGCGCACCCGCGGGUUUGCUAUGGCGAUGAGCAGCGGCGGCAGUGGUGGCGGCGUCCCGGAGCAGGAGGAUUCCGUGCUGUUCCGGCGCGGCACAGGCCAGAGCGAUGAUUCUGACAUUUGGGAUGAUACAGCACUGAUAAAAGCAUAUGAUAAAGCUGUGGCUUCAUUUAAGCAUGCUCUAAAGAAUGGUGACAUUUGUGAAACUUCGGGUAAACCAAAAACCACACCUAAAAGAAAACCUGCUAAGAAGAAUAAAAGCCAAAAGAAGAAUACUGCAGCUUCCUUACAACAGUGGAAAGUUGGGGACAAAUGUUCUGCCAUUUGGUCAGAAGACGGUUGCAUUUACCCAGCUACCAUUGCUUCAAUUGAUUUUAAGAGAGAAACCUGUGUUGUGGUUUACACUGGAUAUGGAAAUAGAGAGGAGCAAAAUCUGUCCGAUCUACUUUCCCCAAUCUGUGAAGUAGCUAAUAAUAUAGAACAAAAUGCUCAAGAGAAUGAAAAUGAAAGCCAAGUUUCAACAGAUGAAAGUGAGAACUCCAGGUCUCCUGGAAAUAAAUCAGAUAACAUCAAGCCCAAAUCUGCUCCAUGGAACUCUUUUCUCCCUCCACCACCCCCCAUGCCAGGGCCAAGACUGGGACCAGGAAAGAUAAUUCCCCCACCACCUCCCAUAUGUCCAGAUUCUCUUGAUGAUGCUGAUGCUUUGGGAAGUAUGUUAAUUUCAUGGUACAUGAGUGGCUAUCAUACUGGCUAUUAUAUGGGUUUUAGACAAAAUCAAAAAGAAGGAAGGUGCUCACAUUCCUUAAAUUAAGGAGAAAUGCUGGCAUAGAGCAGCACUAAAUGACACCACUAAAGAAACGAUCAGACAGAUCUGGAAUGUGAAGCGUUAUAGAAGAUAACUGGCCUCAUUUCUUCAAAAUAUCAAGUGUUGGGAAAGAAAAAAGGAAGUGGAAUGGGUAACUCUUCUUGAUUAAAAGUUAUGUAAUAACCAAAUGCAAUGUGAAAUAUUUUACUGGACUCUAUUUUGAAAAACCAUCUGUAAAAGACUGAGGUGGGGGUGGGAGGCCAGCACGGUGGUGAGGCAGUUGAGAAAAUUUGAAUGUGGAUUAGAUUUUGAAUGAUAUUGGAUAAUUAUUGGUAAUUUUAUGAGCUGUGAGAAGGGUGUUGUAGUUUAUAAAAGACUGUCUUAAUUUGCAUACUUAAGCAUUUAGGAAUGAAGUGUUAGAGUGUCUUAAAAUGUUUCAAAUGGUUUAACAAAAUGUAUGUGAGGCGUAUGUGGCAAAAUGUUACAGAAUCUAACUGGUGGACAUGGCUGUUCAUUGUACUGUUUUUUUCUAUCUUCUAUAUGUUUAAAAGUAUAUAAUAAAAAUAUUUAAUUUUUUUUUAAAUUA